GUGUGAGGGGAACCUGGGAGGGUCAGCUCCGGUCCUGGGUCGGGAGGGGUGGGGGCCAGAGGAUUCAGGGCCGGAGGUUCUGGUGGGGGCCCAGUGGGCGGGACCCGAGGACGGAGGGGCCGGGAGGCCGAGAGGGGCGGGGUCGCGGCGGGGCCUGAGGGACGGAGGCCGGGAUACUUGGGAAAGGAUCCGCCGGCCUUGAACUCCCGCCUCCGCCGCCCCUAGGCCUCAUGGCGGUCCGAGCUUCGUUCGAGAACAACUGUGAGAUCGGCUGCUUUGCCAAGCUCACCAACACCUACUGUCUGGUAGCGAUCGGAGGCUCAGAGAACUUCUACAGUGUGUUCGAGGGCGAGCUCUCCGAUACCAUCCCCGUGGUGCACGCGUCUAUCGCCGGCUGCCGCAUCAUCGGGCGCAUGUGUGUGGGGAACAGGCACGGUCUCCUGGUACCCAACAAUACCACCGACCAGGAGCUGCAACACAUUCGCAACAGCCUCCCAGACACAGUGCAGAUUAGGCGGGUGGAGGAGCGGCUCUCAGCCUUGGGCAAUGUCACCACCUGCAAUGACUACGUGGCCUUGGUCCACCCAGACUUGGACAGGGAGACAGAAGAAAUUCUGGCAGAUGUGCUCAAGGUGGAAGUCUUCAGACAGACAGUGGCCGACCAGGUGCUAGUAGGAAGCUACUGUGUCUUCAGCAAUCAGGGAGGGCUGGUGCAUCCCAAGACUUCAAUUGAAGACCAGGAUGAGCUGUCCUCUCUUCUUCAAGUCCCCCUUGUGGCGGGGACUGUGAACCGAGGCAGUGAGGUGAUUGCUGCUGGGAUGGUGGUGAAUGACUGGUGUGCCUUCUGUGGCCUGGACACAACCAGCACAGAGCUGUCAGUGGUGGAGAGUGUCUUCAAGCUGAAUGAAGCCCAGCCUAGCACCAUUGCCACCAGCAUGCGGGAUUCCCUCAUUGACAGCCUCACCUGAGUCACCUUCCAAGUUGUUCCAUGGGCUCCUGGCUCUGGACUGUGGCCAACCUUCUCCACAUUCCGCCCAAUCUGUACCGGAUGCUGGCAGGGAGGUGGCAGAGAGCUCACUGGGACUGAGGGGCUGGGCACCCAACCCUUUUCCACCUGUGCUUAUCGCCUGGAUCUAUCAUUACUGCAAAAACCUGCUCUGUUGUGCUGGCUGGCAGGCCCUGUGGCUGCUGGCUGAGGGUUCUGCUGUCCUGUGCCACCCCAUUAAAGUGCAGUUCCCUCCGGGCCAUUCUGAAUGUGA